AGAACCCUGAGAGCGCCCGGCACCGCGGCCGCCGACGCAGCAGCCGCCUCCGCUCGUCAACCCCGAGGCGCGCGGGCUCCCGGGCGGCCCCGGCGGGCGCGGCGAGAGGACGCGCCAGGCGGCGCGGGGCGGGCCGCACGCGCCCCCGGCCGCCCCCCGCCCGCGCGCGGACCGGCCCAGCGGAGCCCCGGCGCGGGGAAGCGCCGGCCGGGCGAGGGCGAGGGCGAUGCCGCGGUGACGGCCCCGCCAUGGCUAAGCCCGCGGCGACGGCGGCGGCGGCGUCGGAGGAGCUGAGCCAGGUGCCGGACGAGGAGCUGCUGCGCUGGAGCAAGGAGGAGCUGGCGCGGCGGCUGCGGCGCGCCGAGGGCGAGAAGGUGGGCCUCAUGCUGGAGCACGGCGGCCUGAUGCGCGACGUGAACCGGCGGCUGCAGCAGCACCUGCUGGAGAUCCGCGGCCUCAAGGACGUGAACCAGCGGCUGCAGGACGACAACCAGGAGCUGCGCGAGCUCUGCUGCUUCCUCGACGACGACCGGCAGAAGGGGCGCAAGCUGGCGCGCGAGUGGCAGCGCUUCGGGCGCCACGCGGCCGGCGCCGUGUGGCACGAGGUGGCCCGCUCGCAGCAGAAGCUGCGCGAGCUCGAGGCGCGCCAGGAGGCCCUGCUGCGCGAGAACCUGGAGCUCAAGGAGCUGGUGCUGCUGCUGGACGAGGAGCGCGCGGCACUGGCGGCGACGGGGGCCGCAAGCGGUGGCGGCGGCGGCGGGGGCGGCGCCGGCUCCCGCAGCUCCAUCGACAGCCAGGCCAGCCUGAGCGGGCCGCUGUCGGGUGGCGCGCCCGGCGCGGGGGCCCGCGACGUGGGCGACGGCAGCAGUACGUCCAGCGCGGGCAGCGGCGGCAGCCCCGACCACCACCACCACGUCCCACCCCCGCUGCUGCCCCCCGGGCCGCACAAGGCCCCCGACGGCAAGGCAGGAGCCACACGUCGGUCCCUGGACGACUUGUCGGCGCCGCCGCACCACCGCAGCAUCCCCAACGGCCUGCACGAUCCCUCAUCCACCUACAUCAGGCAACUGGAGAGCAAAGUGAGGCUGCUGGAGGGUGACAAGCUCCUCGCACAGCAGGCAGGCUCCGGAGAGUUCCGCACGCUGCGGAAAGGCUUCUCGCCCUACCACUCGGAGUCCCAGCUUGCGUCCCUGCCGCCCUCCUACCAGGACUCCCUGCAGAACGGCCCGGCCUGCCCCGCACCUGAGCUGCCCUCGCCCCCCUCUGCUGGCUACAGCCCUGCAGGACAGAAGCCCGAGGCUGUCGUGCAUGCCAUGAAGGUCCUGGAGGUACACGAGAAUCUGGACCGGCAGCUCCAGGACAGCUGUGAGGAGGACCUGAGUGAGAAGGAGAAGGCCAUCGUUCGCGAGAUGUGCAACGUGGUCUGGAGAAAGCUGGGAGAUGCAGCCAGCUCCAAGCCCUCCAUACGGCAGCACCUGUCUGGGAACCAGUUCAAGGGGCCUUUGUAGGGCCACUCUUCUGUGGACGUGGACUGGCCCUGCUGGGGGUCCCCAGGGGGAGUUUCAGGCCCCAGACACGGGCAGGACCUCCAGCCCAGCCCCUGUCUUCUUCCUCUGUGGUGAACUGUACAUAGGACGCUGCCCGCCCUGGCCCAGCUGCCAUGGGUCCGAUGCACUGGCCCAAGCCGCCAUCUCCCGCCUCAUACACCAGCAACCUGGGAAGACGAGACGCUGCGACUGUUCCUGCAGCAGAGCGGCCCGGACGCCUCAUUCCCCCUCUGGGCCCUGGGCUCCAUGAGCAAGAGGCUGCAGGCUGCUUCUGAGAUCCAGCCUGGGAACUGUCCAGGCUCCUCUGUCCUGCCUGGGAUGGAGGGGCCACUCAUCAAACCCUCUACUCCCCGGCUGCCACCCACACUGGACAGAGACCACCACUACCUGGGUCUUGACGCAGGUGGCACCACUUCUUGCCCAAAUGCCGUGGCCUGGCCCCAGGCCCCCCAAGCACUGGGUCCCCGGCAUGUGGACAAGGCCACUCACCACAUCUGUGGCUGGCUGGAGGCUGCCCUGGGCCCUUCCUGUGACCCUCAGCCUUGGAGGUCAGGGUGCCCUCACACCUGGGGAUCUGUGCUCAGCCACCCGAUGCCCGCUGCUCCUUGCUUUUGGAGGUCAUCCCCCUCCCCCCCAGUCUCUGCAAUGUCCCCCUGCCACCCUGUCCAGGCUAUGCCCUUCUUGGGCUCCUCCUGCCCCAUGCCUGAGGCACGUCCCUUUUCGUGGUUUACAUGACAGGCCAGUAACAGGAAGGGCCUGGGGAGAGUUUCUGGGCUGAGCCACAUGUGAUUUUCCUGAUGGGCAGCACUGGGCCACAGCUGGGGCUCUGGUUGGCUGUGACCUCCCCCAGGGCCUGGCUGCAUCUUGGGUCCCUGUGGACAGAGCUGUGUAGGCUGCAGAUGAGAGUUCUGUUCUUUUUGGGAAGGAGCGUGUCUGGCCAGGUUCUGCCUUUAGUUUGUGGUGUGACCUUUAGCAGUUCACUCAGCCUGUCUGGGCUCUUGGUGGAAACAGGUCUCUGAGGUUCCUUUUCGGCCAUGCUUAUGGCUCCAGGUCAUCCAGCGCCACAGGGCAGGGGUCCUCACUGAGGGGGCGUGAGCCAACAGCCGACGGCUGAGGGCGGGCCGGGUGGAGCUGAGUUCUGCUGCCUUGCAGUCGCUGCGGGUGGAGAGUUGCCUCCCCACUCUGAGCCCGUGUCCUCAGUAGUAAAAUGGGCAGCAUAAGGCCCUCCUCACAGGAUUCUGGCAUCAAGUGAGAUCUUCAGUGUAAAUGACCAUGUAUAAACUGUAAAGUGCAAUAGAAAACUGUGUGUGUGAGGAAAGUAAGGCCUAGAGGGGGUGAUGUGUGGCACAUGACAGGGAUUUUGAUCCCACAGCUGCAGCACGGGGACAGGCCGCUUCCCCACAUCCGCUCAUGCCACUGUAAGCAGCCCUAGCUCUUGGGUCCAGGACCUCACCAGGUCCUCGUCAGACUCCUGUGCUCUUCCAGGGGCUGCUCAGCCCCACCUGAAGAGCCCAGAGAGGCUGUCUUCCUACCCAGCAGGUCUCAUGCAGGCCCAGGGCUGGGGAUGCAGGCAAGAGGAGGGAGAUGGCCGCCCUGUCCCUCUCCCUAGCUGGCGGCUCUAUUCUGAGCAGUUCUUGCUGCCCGUUUGCUCUCAGGGGAAAGGCUCACGCCCCCCAUCUUAGCCCCAGGGGGGUAAGUGGGUGCUGGUGAUGGGAUGGUGUGGCGCUCCUGCCGUGGGUGUUGCCAGGAGGCUCUUUGGGAAGGAGUGUCGCCCGGUCAGGUGGUGCGCUCCCGGUCACUAGGGGUGUACACGUGAAGUUGGGUGAACACCUGCUGCUCAUGGUACCCAGUGAUUCUUGCCCGAGUGGGCAGCUGAGCAGAGGCCCCUCUGGGUCUUGCAGUCCAAAGAACCGCAGAGUAGCCCAAGGGCUGUGGGUCCAUUUUGAGUGGCAGCCAAGUCUGGGAGCCCGUGUGCAUCAUGUUUGGGUCAGGUUGGCGUGGCCACCACUGAAAUAAGCAAUAAGUACGGGCUCCUGGUACCUGCGGAUCUCCUGCAAACAGGCCCAGAGAACAGCCUUGAAGCCACCUUUCCCCUCAAGGGGACUGACCCUGUCUUUAAUGCUGCAGUGGCAUCCAGGGAUCAGUGGAACAUUGCUUUGAGAACCCUCCUGCUGUUACGGAGGCAGCACAAAGCUGGUGACCCCUGAGCCAACACGGCACUGGGAUGGCUUUCUAGGACAGAACCCUGUCGGCGACUGUCACAUCUCAAACUAAUAGCUGAUUUUAAAAGCCAGCAGCAGCGACGCCAUGUACCUGAGUACAGGUGGCAGUUGCAGAGCCGUGGGCUGUAGAAGGUCAGAUGGGGCUUCCCACAGGGGAAAUCUGGGCAUGCUGUAGCUCAGGGUGACUCCCAGCUCCGUCACUAGCAGGGCGACCCCCUUCCUUCUGGAGCCUUAGCUCUGAAAGCCCCCAGUGGGGGUGCCCUUUCAGAUGCCCCCUUUCCAUUUCAAAGGCUCUGACUCUUGAUCUUGAAGCCGGACGCGGCACUGGCACUCGGCUUCAGUUUCCACUGUGACAGAUGGAGGUCUCCUUUCGCCCCAGCCCAGGUGGCCAAGCCCAUCCUGGCCUCAGAACAUGCUGAGCACAUUUUGUAGGGUGGCACCUUUUUAUCCAAGUUACUAGCUACACAUCAGUGUUUAAAGAGAAAAAAGUGACCUUUCAUUUUUUUUUUCUUGAAACUUGAGGAAACAAGAUACAUACUACUGAUUUUUUUUUUUUCUUAAAACUAAAUGCAUGACUGCAGAGCGGUAGAGGUGUAUAUUUUUCAUACUGUGGGGCAAAGUAUUUGUGCUGCUUUUUGGAGAUGGACUGGAACGUCUGGUUUCUGUCCCCGGGCCCGGCAGCUACGUCUAUUUUCUGUAGAAGGUGCCACAGUGAGACCUGGAGCCACCCCUUCCUGCCCUGGCGCCGUUUAGAGCUGGGAGCCCGUGGACUCCCGGCCUGUUUCUACCUUCUAUUCAACCACUCUGACGUGGGGAGACAAGAAGAAAUAGAACUUUUUGAUAGUGUGGUAAAAACAUUGAUUUGAACUAUUUUAGUAAAAGGAGUAACAAACAAGAUUGUGAUAGUGUCUACUUUGAGCUAGAUAAAUAAAGGCCUCUUUGUGAGCCUCCUGGCUGGGUGCUCAGUGCUUGUUUCUGUCGUGGGUGGCAGGGUCAGCAGGCAGAGACAGGGCCAAGGCCCCUCAAGCACCGCAGAUGGGGGCUCAGUCGGGGCCCCUUCCACAGACAGAGCCGUGGCCCCUCAAGGUGGACAGUGAGGCCGCUGCUCCUCCAGCUGCCUCUGUCUCAUCACAGGCCAGAAGUGGAAAGGGUUUCAAAUCCAAGCCCCCGGGUUCCUGUGUGCGUUCUACGCAGCAAGGCUUCAAAGUUUCAAACUGGUUUGGAACUCAACCAGGUCCUCCAAAGGAAACCAAGGCAGGCACAGGAUGGGGGCAGGCUGGCUUGGCAGGCAGCUGUGCGGAUCCACCCAGAGUGCCUUGGGAGGCAGUGGGGUUGGCUGUGGCUGCUGUGAGCUGCAGCCAGGCCUCUCCCGCGUCCCCAGGGUCUGGAAGGAGGGCCUCUGCACAUUUUAUAAGCCACAGACUGCGAAGGCCUGGAGCCCCACCUUCCACCCAUAACAAAGAAAGGGAUAGUUUCAGAACUGCUUUUAUUUGGAUAACUGACUGAAGGAGUCUCAUUUGUAACCAAGAUGGAAUUCACAGUAUGUUGUUACAUUCACACUUAAAAAAUAUAUCUCUAUGUACAGGAAUUUGCAAAGAGAUGUAAACAUACAUUAAUUUCCAAGUACAUUUCUCCCCUUCUCCCUGGAGGAAAAAAAAAAAGCCAUCCAAUGAGGCAACCCCUUCAAAAUAAUUUUAAUACAAAGGAUGCAAACAUCUAUAAAUGAAAAAUGUGGUUCUUCUGCCCCUUCUGGGUGUCAUGGGAGAGAAUGUCACCGAAUGAAAAUGACAACAGCUUGGCUUCAGAUGGAAUUGGACUAUUUAAAAUUGAGUUUCCAGGAAAAAUAGGCACUGAUUUCUAGAAGGAAAUUAACUCCUUACCGAAGCUAUUUAUUGAGCCAAUAUGGCUGGUUAACGUCCUCACUAGUAUAAAGUAACCCAGUGCAGGACUCUCAGACAUUAGCUGAACCAAGUGUACACAGUCAGACUGCAAGGGCACUGAUGAGGCUACUCUGAAAGCUGGUUGUCCCCGUCCUCUAGGUGUGAGGACCACUCUGAUUUUAUCCCAGGGGCCCGGUCCAUUCUUCCCAUACUGCAACUGUCGUGCAUUAUACAAGGUACCCUGCUGCUUACCCACUUCAACUACUCUGCAAGUCGAUUAGAAAAUCUUGUUAAAAAAACAAAGAGGGAAAAAAGGCUCACGUUAUCUCAUCCAGGCUGCCCGCCCCAGCCCCCCAACUGGAGGCAUGCCGGGUGGGGGAAUGGGCGGGGGCACAGGAGGCUGUCCUCCAGGGGGGACGGCAGGAGGUGGGUAGCUGGCUGGCGGCAGGCCCAACCCUGGAGGAGGAUGAGGGGGGACUGCGUGGGUAGGCGGGAGGCGUGGGGGUGGGGGUGGGAAGUUGGGGUUGUAGGUGGGUGGGGGUGGGGGGUAGCCAGGAGUAGGGGGUGGGAUGGCAGGUGGGGGGAAGGAGGCUGGGGGAGGAGGCACAGGUGGCGGGGGCGGGUUGGGCGGGUAGACAUGGGGGUGGUAGGGCAGGUGUGCAGGUGGGCCGUAGGCGGGGGGCAGGGCACCGUAGGAGGGUCCCUCGGUCUUCAUCAUGGACUGCAGGCUCUGGUAGCCCUCUCCAGACAUGUAGGAGCUGGUGGUGGACAUCCCGGUCAUGUAGCUGGAGGGGGGUGGGGGCGGGGGCCGGUGUGGCAGCGGCGGUGGCUGGUGCACAGGGGCCGGGUGGGCCGGAGGGGGAAUCUGGACUUUGGGGAGGUCAGUGGCAUCCACAGGGCCCGGCGGCUCAGCCUCACCUAAGGCAGCAGCGAGGGGAGGCUUCCGGUCUGCAGGAGAGAGACGCAUCAGUGCCCGGCCUCCGCCAGCAAUGGUUGCUUUUUCAGUGCCUCCUGGCCCUUCAGGGCCAUCUUUACAGAGGAGCAGGGAGCAGCUGCCCGCCUCCUCUGUGGCCCAACGCAUGGGCCCAUGCCCCAUGUCCUGAUGCCACCAGAUGUCUCCCCACCAUCUGUCAAGAAGGCCCUCCACCCUGUCUGCGACGACCUGGGGUUUUCCCUCCCUCAGCCCUGACCACACCACCUACAGGCAGUCUCGGCAGCACCCGAAGCCCCCUUGUGCCCUGGCCCCAGCCCCCUCUUCCUAGUGCAAAACGUGUGGGGGCUCCUCUGUUUUUCUGCCUUCAGAAACUGACCCCAGGGGUCAGGGCCACACUGAACUCCUGUCUGCAGCAGUGGCAUUUUGCAGAAAACCUCAGAGUUAGUCAAAUGAAUGUGAUGGCACUUAAAACAAUUCUGUACAAGUCUCUGACAUUCCCGGUGUACCCAUCGAAGCAGCAAUUCAGGUUCUAUUCUACUCAAGAGAGGCUACAUCAAACCCCACUGUGUGCUCUCAGAUAGCAGCCUCCUUGAGAGGAGUGUGUGCAUGUGUGUGCGUGUGCGUGCUGCGUGCGUGCUGCAUGUCUGUGCGUGCUGCGUGUGUGUGCGUGCUGCGUGUGCAGCAGGGACAGGCAGCACUAGGUGUUGAGCACGCCCAAGAUACUCGUGCUCAGAACCAGCCUCAGGCCCCUCCCACAGCGCCUCCCAACCCAUGAGCCCUCACGCCCCCUUCUGCCAAAGCCUUAUUUAACAUGUUUUGGCCUGUGAUCCCGGGUCACCGUCAGACCACUGGAAAAUGACAUCGCAACACCCCACCACAGGUAGCCAAACACACAGAAUGAGUGUCCUUUCCCAAGGCAGCCCAGGAGACAGACCACAGGAGCAACAUUUCUGGUUCCAGAGAACAUAGAGAGGACAAAGCCACGAAGAUGCUUCUGGUUCCCCAGGCACUUGGGUUAGGCAAGGCACAGCACGACAUCCUGGUUGGGUAGACGUGGCCAUUGGCACACAACCCGUUUGAUCUUGCCAAAGCGAGCAUGAGCAGGAUUUCAUCAGGUCGGUAACAGGUGUGCCACUGGUGUGCCACAUCAGCACCCCGCCAGCCUACCGGGUAGGAAGGUCAUAUGUGCCUGGCCUUAGAUAACUGGCUUUGGCUCCAGGUCAGGGCCAGAUGCCCUGUGGUUCUAGGAGCUGACUAAAAAAGAGGUGCAGAAAAGUGCUGACACCCUUCAAUGCCUCCUGUGUGUCACUCCACAGCCACCUGGGCCCACAGGCCUGCUCCUCCACCUUGCAGAAAUCAACUUUUCCAACACUCGACCCUGUAGCCUGAAUCUUCAAGUCACCAGUGUGCCUGCCCUUGUGCUGUGUGACUGAGCUGGAACAGCAAGUGGGGGUCUCUCCUGGGCACCCCAUUCCCUCUCUGUACACUUGCUCCUGACCAAGUCCCACACACUGCCACCAAACUGCUCCCUAAACAUCACUGCUGACCUGAAUGCCUCUUCCCAUGGCCUAGGGCCUCCCAGGAAGCGUACUUCCCUCCCUUCCUCACGGCCCAGCUUUACUGCGCCUCCCAGGCCCUGCUCUCUUCAGCCAUGGCCUCCUGGCAGUGUAUCUGGCACCCAGGUCCCACUCAAGUCCCAGGCCUACUCCUGGCUAUCUGUAAUGGGGGAGGGAGCAGAGCUCUGAGGCCUCCACAGCAGCUACUCAGUGCCCUGGAGGUAGCAGCACCCCUGUGGCUGCCCCAGGCUCCCCAGAUAAACCACCCAUCUCCUCAGUGAAGGCACAGCCCCAGGCUCGGACCAGGGGAACUGCACUUGGCGAGGAGGUGCUCCAUAAAUGCUUCAUGAGCAACCACAGGCAUUUAAGUAAGGUUCAUAUUGAAUUGGGGGUUUUGGGAUUUGGCCCCAAAGUGGAAAAUGACGCCUCUGUUCUCCCAAAGCACAAACACUAUCAUGAUUGAGUAGGAACAGAAAUGUAAUCUGUGGCACAUCUGUUACGGGCACACAGUGCUGUCAGCCCCAGUGUGAGCCACGUGCACCGACCAACAGUGAGUGUAGCAGGCUGGAGGAGCUGCUGACAGAGGCUUGGAAGCCUCCGGAGUAUCGACCACCUUUUGGAGAGCAAGCACAGGUCACUCUGGCCUUCUCUAGCGCAUCACCUUCUGAAAUGGUGCCACAGGUAAAGAAUGCCAUCUACUUUACAGCUUUUCUCCUCUAUUGCCAGCGGUAUCAGAGAGGCUUUCCAGCUUACCAUGUACUACUUGUUGAGAACUUUUCACUCUUUCAUUUACUCUCUGUACAAUUGCUUAUUCUUCAGAAUGCACUAAGACGACACACUGCCAAUAGGAAGCAGGUGUAGGGGCGGCCGGAGCCUAGUAGCCACAGUAACCCUGCCUCUAUCUCAGAAGGCGGGGUUUGGCUUUCUUUCCUAAAACUGAUUCUAAUACAAUGUGUAGUUUAGCAUUUCUGGAUGUGAGAGGUCGGAAAAUAUUCAGAUAUACUUAACAAUUUACAACAUUCUCAAAAUACCUGGUCAAAAUCAGAACUUUGAGACACGGUCUCCCUCUCACCCAGGCUGGAGUACGGUGGUGCAAUCAUAGCUCACUGCAGCCUUGACUGCCCAGGGCUCAAAUGAUCUUCCCAUCUCAGACUCCUAAGUAGUUGGGACUACAGGUGUGUGCUACCACACCUGGCUAAUUUUUUAGACAGGGUCUCACUUUGUUGCCCAGGCUGACCUCGAACUCCUGGGGUCAGGUGAUUCUCCUGCCUCCGCCUCCCAAAGUGCUGGGAUCAAAAACACAAGCCAUUGUGCCCAGCCCAAGAACAAUUUUGCAAAGAUUCCUGCCUGUGGCUGACAUUGUCAAUCUGGGCCCCAGUCUCCCUUUUCUAAGUUCCCAGGACCUGCUGCGUCCAACAUUCAGAGGCGAUGUGCACAGCUGGCCAAGCUGCUUCAGCAGAUGCUUACCUGGAGGUGGGUGGGCUGGAGGCAACGGUGGAUGAGUGGUCUCAAUUUUGGGGAUUUUAGGUGGUGGUGGUUCUACAAAGAAAAAGCAGAUUAGAAAACCACUCAUACUUCUUCACAUGAAUAAGCAUGUCAUAAAGAAAAAUGUACUGGCAGAGAUUUCUUUGGGAGAAAAACAACAGAGAUGACCAAGGCUUUAAGGGAACUUGAAGAAGGUUUCAGCUAAACCAUUAUGCAUGAAUCCUGUUAACAAAUUAAAUGCCACCUCCCUCCAAAAGACCUGCGAGCUUCCCACAGGCAGCCCAUUUUCCAUGUCUACCUAAGUUUCCUUGCUGACCACUUCACUCAAGUCCUUCCGACCAUGUGAGACCAGCAGAGCAACGUCUUCAUGAGCAUGUAUGACCUAUCUGGAGUCCUCCCUGGUACAGAGGACACAAAGAAGGGUCCAGAGUAGCAACAUCAUGUCACUGAGUCCCCUGAGGGUUCCACAAGAGAAUCUCUAUCUUUUCAUUCUUAGACAUAGUUUAUUCUCUCUUUCCCAAAUACUGACUUCCAGUUGGCAGCAUGUCAGAAGCAGCACAUUAACUGGAGUCAGCAGAGCUCUGGAGGUUGACACACUGAUGGCAGGAAGAAUGUGCCGCUCACAAAAGCCCAGCAGUCAGGACCCCUUGAGGUGGAGGAAACAGCCCACCCUUCCGGGGUCAGGCAGCGGCACGCAGCCAGAAUCCACAAUGACAGCACUAGGUCUCCAAGGCAGCCCAAGGGAAGUCCAAUCUCAUCCGUUUAAGAAGGCAGCGUGCACAUCACAACUGAAAAAGAACCCUAUUUUUCUGUUUGCAUGCUGAGGCUUUUUCUUCCUGAAAUGUACUUUCUUCUGGCUUGUACACCACUCAGAUCUGAGUCUCCUCUGCCAUCACUGGCCUCUUUCUCUGGAUUUCCUCCAUCUCAAAUACAGGCUCAAUUUAAGUUCCAGGGACUUCCUCUCUCUUCACCCUCUUCCUCAGAGUCCAAAGCCCCUCUCUAAGUGGACAACUACAAACCUACAUUUCUAGCGUCCAUCUUGCCACCAAAACCAUGGCCCAUCCCUAGACCCACCAAUCAGCACCUCACACUCUACCUUUUGCCUCUGUAUCCUAUAACUGCUAUUACUCUCACCUCAGGGACCCACCUCCUGCCUUUUUCCACAGCUGGUAAUAGUUAGCUAAAGCCGUCUACAUCAGGGCUGUCCAACAGCAAUAUAACUGAGAGCCACAUAUCUACAAUUUUAAACUUUCCAGGAGCCAUUUUAUUUUUUGAGACAGGGUCUCGCUCUGUCACCCAGGCUGGAGUGUAGUAAUGUAAUCAUGGCUCACUGCAGCUUCAACCAACCAGGCUCAAGUGAUCUUGCUGCCUGAGUCUCCCAAGUAGCUGGGACCAUAGGUGUGGCGCCACCACGCCGAGCUGAUUUUUAAGUUUUGUGUAGUGAUGGGGUCACCCUAUGUGGCCCAGUCUGGCCUGGAACUCCUGGGCUCAAAGCAUGCCUUGGCCUCCCAAAGUGCUGGGAUUACAAGUGUGCCAGGAACCACUUUAACAAGAAAAAGGAGCACUCCAGCCUGCAUUAACAGAGCAAGACUCUGGAAAUAAAAGGAAAAAGGAUAAAAUUUAUUUAACCCGAUAGAUCGAAAAUUUUAUUUCAACAUGUAACCAAUAUAAAGCUUUACUAAUGAGAUGUCUUACGUUCUCCUUUCUUGGAAAUCUCUGUGUAUUUUGCAUUGUCAGUGCUUCAGAAUUUGACCCAGUCACAUUUCGAGUGCUUGCAGCCCUCUGCAGCCAGUAGCCUUCGGCAUGGCACAGUGCAGCUGAGUUCCUCUAUAAAGCUUCCUCCGGAUCUGCCCUUCCUGCCCCGCAGCCAGCAUGCUGAGGCCACCAUGUUUCCCAUGAGUGCCAGCAAGAUUCUCCCCAUUCCUAACCACUUGCCCUAUUUACUGCUGCCAGGGGACUCCUUCUCAAAUGAAUUUAGACUCUGCCAUUCCCCUGCUAAAUCUCCAAUGGCUUCCCUUGCCUCUGCCAAACUCACAGUCCUCCAGGUAAACUCUGUGAUCUGGUCCUAACCCACAUUUUAGAUCCUAUCAGAAGCUAUUGCCUUUCAAUUCAUCACAUUCCAGAAAGACUCCUCUCCAUUUCCCCUGAUUCUCAAUUCCUUUGCUCACUUGCGUACUUCCAACUUAUUGCUCCAUCCUCCCCCUCUGCUCUCGCUGCUCAAAUGCAACUCUUCCUUCAAGGUCAUAUAUAGUUUGUUUCCUGCCUCUGACAGACCUGCACGUCAACUCAAUUGCAUUUCAUGUGGCAUGGAGUGUAGCCCGUUCUUGUGUCUAACAUUUAAUGUCGGUCAAUUUGAAGCUAAUUAAAAAAUUCACCUGUAGGCUGGGCACGGUGGCUCAUGCCUGUAAUCGCAGCACUUUGGGAGGCUGGGGCGAGCAGAUCACCUGAGGUCGGGAGUUUGACACCUGCCUGACCAACAUGGAGAAACCCUGUCUCUACUAAAAAUACAAAAUUAGCCAGGCCUGGUGGUGCAUGCCUGUAAUCCCAGCUACUCGGGAGGCUGAGGCAGGAGAAUUGCUUGAACCCAGGAGGCGGAGGUUGUGGUGAGUUAAGAUUGCACCGCUGCACUCCAGCCUGGGCAACAAGAGUGAAACUCUGUCUCAAAAAAAAAAAAAAAAUUCACCUGUACUGAACUCAUCAUUCCCUCAAAUAUACUGGAAAAAAAAAAAAAGUAGCUCUAUCAUAACUGGAAGAUUUCACAGCAGUUUAAUGAAUGGAACUAAGAACCGAGAACAUGGUUCUAAGAACCAGGAACUACUGGAACUAAGAACCAAGUAACAAAGAAAGACAAAUGAGUCAAUAGGGUCUGUGCCUUCAAAGAGUUCAGUAUGAUAGGUGGACUGACCCUGUGACAAAACAUUUCUAACUUUCUGUUUUGUAAUUGUUCCAAUUUUGCUCACUCCUUCUGUUUAUUUCCAAUAUUGACAUGAACUAACUUUGGGUUCUAGACAUGUGACAGCACCUCAACCCAAGUGUGUUUCAAAGAGGCCUUGCCUGCAAGGGCAGCUGGGCUGGGCCGGGCUGGUGCUGUCCGGGCAGCACACCACCCCCUACUGCCCCCCCGCAUCUGCUGUGGCUUGGUGCUUGGGAGAGGACUCCUGCUGCUGUGAUGGGGGUAAAUAGUCUCUAAAAAUAAAAUUGCAGCAACAGUUCUCCUACAGCCAUAAUUAUACUUUUAUAUAUGUUACUGAGUACAUUUUUAUUGCCAGUAAUGUUUUCUGUACUGAUAGCUUCGUAAGAGCACAAUUUUAGAAUCUAUGAUCAGGUGAUGAACAGAAAGACAAUGCUGAUGGAAAAGUUUUGUAUGAGCUCUAAAGUUAAGAUUUAAGGCCAAUUUAGAUCUGAAAAGAAACAAUGUUGGCUAAGAAUUUAAAGUUUUGCAUAUAAACACAUAAAACUAAAAAAACAUCAGAACAGGAAAUUACCUGCUGCUUUGUUCUCUUCUUUGGGAGAAACAACCUGUUACAAAAGAAAAUACACAAUUGUUAACUGGGAUCCUGAGUAUGAUGAGAAAAAAAUGGAUUAUCCAGGUACCACCAGAAUCAGCGACGGCAGUCACUGUGAACAGCCUCGGACAAAAAUUAUUUCUAGCCUGAACUUUCAGGGCAAACCACGGCACCUACCAGAUCAUCAUUUCUGCUCCCUUCCUCUUUCCAUUUACCAAAUAAGACAGAAUGACUAGCUUUCCUGAAUGGUGAGUUCUGAGUAAACACUAAGUUUCAGGACCACUUGGGUGCAGGAAACGGUCCACUGUUUGGGGUCAGGCAGCUGCACAGAAGCAGCAUGCACAACGACACUGCUAGGACACGGCAACGACACCGACAGGCUUCAGAACCCUGGCAGGGAUGAAACAGGCAGCAGGGCUGGAGCCGGGCAGAGAGCCCCCUCCUGGUUCUCAGAGGCAGCCUGUCCUUGGAGCACCUUUGUUUUCAGGCUCCCCACCGACAAGCAGUCGGACUGCGAGUUUCGGCGAACACCCCCUGCUUCCGGUGUUCCCUGUGCUCGCUUAGAAAUGGGAACAGUGCUCAGGUGUUGCCGCCACCUGGAAAGCCUGCUCUACCCAGGGCCUGCUUUAGCCCACUCACCACGGCUCGCUUAACCUGUCGGGGAGAACUGGGCUGCGGAGAGGGUUUCUUGGGCUGUUGGGCUGGCUGCUGCUGCUGGGCUGGUUGCUGGGGGUCCUUCUGCUGGGGCUGGGAUGGUUCGGAGCUUUGAGACGGCUGUGACUGCUGUACUUGCGGCACUUGUGGUGUAGGCUGAAGAGAUGGGGGCUGUUGCAGCUGAUGGGGGGUGUGAUGAGGCAUCUGUUGUUUUCCUUGUGAGUAAAGAUCCAGGAUUUGGUGGCAGAUGUCUAAAUGAUAGCCAACAAUUACAUUUUACACAAAUUGGUAUUUUAAAUAAAAUUUUACCUGGAUAAAGAAUCAGUUAUGAUACCCCUACGAGGACCUAAGCAUGAAUCACAUUUACAACUCACCCCAUCUUCGUUGUGUGCAACACUGGUGUGUAUUUUUAGUUUACCAAAAGUAUGUGUUUGGACAAAGUGGAAACUAUUAGAUAAUUUAAUUAAUGAUGCUUCUGAAAUAUUGCUCACAUAUGUCUAUCUGGGAAAAUCCAUUCUUGGGACUCAGGGUACACAUGGAAGAAUCAUCUCAACAUGGAACACCCUCACGAGAACGCUUAGCAUGCCUGGUACCUUCCAAAACGUCGACCGGGACAUCUUGAACAAACUGCUCCCACCAUCUCCUAUACAUGGGUUUGGAGGUCCAUUCUUGUAUUUCAAAUUUGCACAAACGUCCUGCGAGAUACAUCACUGCUACUGCUAUGAUCUCUGGUUCCCACUGCAGUGACAAGGUGGUGCAGAGACUAGUUCAACAAGAAAAAAAAAGGUUAGAUAAUAUGAUCUAAUAUUUAUGAUUAAACCAGUGCAUGGAGAUGCCAUAACUAACCAUUAAUUUGCUUAUUCUCCCCUAAAUUUAAUUAAAGUACUAUAAAUAAAUAAACUCAAGUCUUUACUCUUCUAAAGGUACCCGACUAAGUUACUUUAACCAUAGUUAGUAAUUUCUCUAUUCCUUAAAGAAUCAGAAGAAUUCUAGCACAUCCAAAAAUUGCUACACCAAUGAAAAUGACUUAUGUUAUUUAAACUGUUGAAAUCCUAGCCACUCAACUGUUUCUUCAAAUGAAAUCUUAUGGAGGAAGUCAAAUGUAAGAGAAGCUUCACUGACUGCAGUGGGAUGGGGCUGGCAGCAACUCCAUUCACAGGCAUUCUGUUUCCCACCACGGCCCCUCAUUAGAUCCCUGGCCUCUCAAAAGAGUGUUAAGGCUCUAAAACUAUACCAGGAAGUAUAUUUUUGCAAAACCAAAUGGGCUCUAAGUAAUUAGUUUUCAAAAUUCUCCAGUGUAUUGUUUUGGACUUAUGUUUCAGACUGGUGAUAAAAUUUCAGCACCUCACAACACCAUGACACGGCAGGGCAGAAGGAAACCCUCUGCCGGGAAGCAGAUGACCUGGACGUCAGCCCCAGCUUUGCCAUUAACUGGCUCCUCAAGCCAGGGCAAGUCAGUUUCUUCUGACACAAAAUGAGGGGUUUAGAUGAAAUGGUCCAUAAAGUCUCUGCCUAUUUUAAAAUACUGUAAUUAAUCAACAUUUGAACAUGUAUACCUGUCAUUUACAAAUGUCCAUGCCAUUUGAACCAACUUUUGAAUUUUGUUUUUAUCACCUAGAAAUGGGGACAAAAAGGUAAAUUAAUAGCAAUAGAAAAAUUCACAGGCAGCAUCAAGUAUUUAUUAAAAACCUACCACGUGUUCAGCACCACUCAAAUACACAGCAAAGAGCUUUUGCGUGGGAAACAAGGAUGAAUGAUGUGGGUCCACAUCCUACCCCUUCUUCCUCCUCAUGACCUACGCUGAACCACCAUGUAUGGAAAACCUGGCUCCAAGGCUAAGUUUAUUAGUCCAUUUAAAAAAUUCUGCCUCAUUUUCCUGCCUCUCCCAUCACUUGGCAACUGGAUGACAGAGCCUGUUUAUACAUAAAAGGAAACAGCAUUAGCAGCUGCAAUGCUGAAUUGACUGAGCAAGCCAUGCCCUUGGUAUUUCACACAUCAAACUUUGUUUUCCGCUUUUGAGAAGCGUAAUUUGAGUGUCAUCAAAUUAUAAAGACUUGAUUUCAGAAUGAAAAAAUUCUUCUGAAAACUUUCUUCUUACCUUUGAGUUGCUUUGCAUAUUUUAGUAGGAACUGGUAUGGAUGUUCUACCUGUAAAUCAAACUUGAUGGUCUGCAGUAAGAUUCUCUCCAGAACCAUUACUUCCUCCUAAAAAUCAAUCACAAAUGUUAGGACAGUAAUUACAAUUGCAGGUCUCAAGCAGCAUUACAAAAGUGAGCUUUCCUGUCUAUUUAUUCUCUCUUCAAGUUAUAUUUUAGCAACUGCCUUUCCUUCCUUUCUCUCCCACUCAGACUUUUAACAUGCUCAGAGACACUGAUAAAUUCUGAAAAGAUCUCAAACAGGAAGACAAAGCAGAGGUGUAAUGUAAAAAAAAAUACUGAAAACAAAAGAUCCUUAAAAAUAUUAUUAUUUUCAAUACAUACAUGAGUCUCCCUUUACAAAACAGAUCUUUACGUUAUUGAUAAUUUGACUAAAUUGUAAUUUCUUUCAAGACCUCAAAUUUUAAAAAUGCAAUCUUUUAGGAAUUUUCAUUGAAAACAUUUUAAGCAAGAAAGAGUUUAUGAUAGCCAGCCUCAUGAAAACUCAGAGAUAAAUUGUACCAGUGUGUGUGUAUGUGUGUGUAUAUAUACUCAUGUACACAUAUAGUGUAUUACGUGCAAAUGGGGGCAAAUCAAUUUUGUGUUUAAAUCUUUCAUUUAUUUGAAAUAAAUCAUCCCAACAACA